GGAAAAAUAGGAGUAAAAUUCAUUGCAGUAAACCCACAUGGGUGACUGGGACAUGAGGGAUGGAGCUGCCCAUCUGUUCACAGGCAAUACACACAUACCAGUGCCUUCAAGGCACCAGGUAUAUGAAAAGCCUUGGUCUAUGUCCAUGCAAAUCUGUCUUGCUGCGUAGUUUCCUUGUGGAGAGUUCAUAUCAGCAAGAGCACAGAGGACUGGGGGUAUGUGGAAGUGAGGGCUGCAGGUGGAGAUGGUGUUCUUCUUGGAGGUGGAAUGCAGAACCAGAAUCUGGAACCCAGAAUAUUACAUUCUUAGUGUUGCUAGGCUUGGGAAGAGGAAGUGGGGGAGGUCUGGCCUGGAGGGGAAAAUUAAGGGGCUGAUUAAAGUGAGGCUGACCCUGAAAAAUGAACAGUAUUCCAUCCACAUAAGACAGAAAGCUCAGGAGACGUUAUUAGUCAUGGUCCCCACCCAAUGACAGUGACUUGUCCACCAUGGAGAUGCUGACUGCGGUGAUGGAGUGGAAAUGAGCCCCAGGCCAGGCACCCACCCAGCUCCACCCUGAGCAGCUGCAUGUGGUUGAGCAGGUCCUUUAACUUCUUUGGGCCAGCCUCUUUAAAUUGUCAGUAAAAUUGUCAUGAGGAUUAAAUGAGCCUCACUUUUUUCAUCUGCAAAAUGGUAACAACGACACUUUCCCUAGAGGGGCCAUGAAGAUGAAAUGAAAUAAUAAGCAUGACGGAUGGUCCUGGUGCUAGCCUCACAGCUCACCUGUUCCUAGAGCAAUGUCUUCCCAGCAGCAGCAGCGGCAGCAGCAGCAGUGCCCACCCCAGAGGGCCCAGCAGCAGCAAGUGAAGCAGCCUUGUCAGCCACCCCCUGUUAAAUGUCAAGAGACAUGUGCACCCAAAACCAAGGAUCCAUGUGCUCCCCAGGUCAAGAAGCAAUGCCCACCGAAAGGCACCAUCAUUCCAGCCCAGCAGAAGUGUCCCUCAGCCCAGCAAGCCUCCAAGAGCAAACAGAAGUAAGGAUGGACUGGAUAUUACCAUCAUCCACCAUCCUGGCUACCAGAUGGAACCUUCUCUUCUUCCUUCUCCUCUUCCCUCCAGCUCUUGAGCCUACCCUCCUCUCACAUCUCCUCCUGCCCAAGAUGUAAGGAAGCAUUGUAAGGAUUUCUUCCCAUCGUACCCUUCCCCACACAUACCACCUUGGCUUCUUCUAUAUCCCACCCCGAUGCUCUCCCAGGUGGGUGUGAGAGAGACCUCAUUCUCUGCAGGCUCCAGCGUGGCCACAGCUAAGGCCCAUCCAUUUCCCAAAGUGAGGAAAGUGUCUGGGCUUCUUCUGGGGUUCCACCCUGACAAGUAGGGUCACAGAGGCUGGUGCACAGUUUCUGCCUCAUUCCUCUCCAUGAUGCCCCCUGCUCUGGGCUUCUCUCCUGUUUUCCCCAAUAAAUAUGUGCCUCAUGUAAUAAA